CUUCCCCUCCGGACUCUGUGCUAGCACUGUAUACGUUUGCAGUUCUCUGCCCAGCCGCUGUGGAAAAUCGGCCUCGAAGUGAUUGAAAUUCCCUGUUUAUAUCAGGCGGCUUCUUUCAGAUCCAUCGUCUUUCUCCCGGAGUAUGAAUGGAAGGAUUCAGUAUGCGCUUCACAUUUGUAUGUCUCUGGCCAUUCUCAAACCAGGCCCUUCCCUUUGAAAAGUCUUUUGCAUGGGAUGUUCACUUCUUAGACGCAAGGUUGUGUGCCCUGGUUUCAUCGUCUAACGCGUUAGAAGGCGCUUUCAUUUCUUCAUGGGUGUUGAGCGCCGACCACUGGGGUGGCCUCUGCCUUCGUAGACCUGCGCCUGGUGAGACGGACAGAUGCUGAACAAAACGAUGUGAAAUUACCGCAGUGGCAGUGCCCCAGAGGAGAGUUCCACGGUGAUAGGAGAAUGAGGGAAUUUGGCUUCUUUAGGGAGGGAAAGGAAGGGUUUCUGAGCAAGUGAGGAUCGAGCUGAGAGCUGAAGGGCUAGCAGGAGUUAACUAAGGAAAGAGAAAAGGAAAAGACAUUCCAGACAAAAAGACUAACUUGUCAGAAAGCCCUGUGGCGGAAGGGAGCUUUUCCAAUAUGAAGAACUGAGCCUGGAGAGAUGGGAUGAGGGGGAGUGUCGAACCUUUUAGGCUUUGUAAAGGAGUUUUGGUUUUCUCCUAAUAGCAAUGGGAUAUCUUCCAAGGAAUCUCAAUCAAAAGGGAGAGAUGGCUCCGAUUGGAAUGUCAUCCCUGGCUGAAGAGUAGAGGAAGCGAAAAAAAGAAGAGUUAAAGAGGCAAAUGCAGGGAACCCGACGAGGAGGCUAUUGCCGUAGUAGUUCACAUGGUGAAAAGAAUGGAGCGUUUGUAUUAAUGAUUAUGGAUUCACUCUUUGAACAAAUUUCUGGCAGCUUUUUAGUUUUGAAAGUGAGAAGUUUCAGACUCUCACUGAGGUAUUCUGUAGUUUUUUCACUCUAAAAGGAAACUAGUAGAGUUCAUGUAACACACACUAAUGCCUCUUUACAUUUAACUUUAGUAUGUGAUAGCUGAAAUUUCCAGCUGUGAUAAAUUGGGAAAUCCUUUGAUUUAAAAGAAAAACAAAGGCGGGUGAGGGUGAGAGUAUAUGCCACGGUGUGUAGAAUCCUUUAGACUCUUAAGAAGACACAAGGCGGCUGGGCGUGGUGGCUCACGCUUGUAAUCCCAGCACUUUGGGAGGCCGAGGCGGGCGGAUCACGAGGUCAGGAGAUCGAGACCAUCCUGGCUAACACGGUGAAAGCCCGUCUCUACUAAAAAUACAAAAAAAUUAGCCGGGCAAGGUGGCGGGCGCCUGUAGUCCCAGCUACUCGGGAGGCUGAGGCAGGAGAAUGGCGUGAACCCGGGAGGCGGAGUUUGCAGUGAGACGAGAUCACGCCACUGCACUCCAGCCUGGGCGACAGAGUGAGACGCUGUUUCAGAAGAAAGACACAAGAUUAGCUUUGAAGUUUAAAUCCAAUGGAGAAGACUCAAGAAACAGUCCAAAGAAUUCUUCUAGAACCCUAUAAAUACUUACUUCAGUUACCAGGUAAACAAGUGAGAACCAAACUUUCACAGGCAUUUAAUCAUUGGCUGAAAGUUCCAGAGGACAAGCUACAGAUUAUUAUUGAAGUGACAGAAAUGUUGCAUAAUGCCAGUUUACUCAUCGAUGAUAUUGAAGACAACUCAAAACUCCGACGUGGCUUUCCAGUGGCCCACAGCAUCUAUGGAAUCCCAUCUGUCAUCAAUUCUGCCAAUUACGUGUAUUUCCUUGGCUUGGAGAAAGUCUUAACCCUUGAUCACCCAGAUGCAGUGAAGCUUUUUACCCGCCAGCUUUUGGAACUCCAUCAGGGACAAGGCCUAGAUAUUUACUGGAGGGAUAAUUACACUUGUCCCACUGAAGAAGAAUAUAAAGCUAUGGUGCUGCAGAAAACAGGUGGACUGUUUGGAUUAGCAGUAGGUCUCAUGCAGUUGUUCUCUGAUUACAAAGAAGAUUUAAAACCGCUACUUAAUACACUUGGGCUCUUUUUCCAAAUUAGGGAUGAUUAUGCUAAUCUACACUCCAAAGAAUAUAGUGAAAACAAAAGUUUUUGUGAAGAUCUGACAGAGGGAAAGUUCUCAUUUCCUACUAUUCAUGCUAUUUGGUCAAGGCCUGAAAGCACCCAGGUGCAGAAUAUCUUGCGCCAGAGAACAGAAAACAUAGAUAUAAAAAAAUACUGUGUACAUUAUCUUGAGGAUGUAGGUUCUUUUGAAUACACUCGUAAUACCCUUAAAGAGCUUGAAGCUAAAGCCUAUAAACAGAUUGAUGCACGUGGUGGGAACCCUGAGCUAGUAGCCUUAGUAAAACACUUAAGUAAGAUGUUCAAAGAAGAAAAUGAAUAAUGUUAAGCCAUUCUUGAUUGGACCUCAUAGCUUAUUUUAGUUAAUCUUUUUUUUGUCUUUUAGCCUUACCACCUUUUAAAAAAUUUGUUAUUCUCCAGAAACAGUAAAUAGGUGAGUAGGGGUGGUGCAAGUGAAUUCGUUUUCAUUUAGAAGCCCCUCUGUACAGAUAAUCAAAAUUCAAAGUUGAAAGAAUCAAAAGCAGCCACAGUUAUGUAGGUCUGAUUUGAAUGUCAUAAUUGCAGUGACAGGACAUUGCCACCAACUCUAUCCUACUACCAUCAAUGUUGUGUUUAUUCCGUCAAUAAAAAAGACUUGCUUCCAGGAAUUUUUAUCCAUACACUUUCUAACUGUACUAUCUGGGCAGUUCCAAGCCAGUUUCUAUUAGCUAGCUGGACCAAAGACCACAAAUCUCUUUUUUUCCUAAACGCUGCUGUAAGGAAUAUCUCACUUUUCCCCCCGGAAACACCCUCACUGAAGUCUUCUAUGAAAAGGCUGAUAAUGGGCUGGGCGCGGUGGCUCACGCCUGUAAUCCCAGCACUUUGGGAGGCCGAGGCGGGCAGAUCACGAGGUCAGGAGAUCGAGACCAUCCUGACACGGUGAAACCCUGUCUCUACUAAAAAUACAAAAAAUUAGCUGGGCGUGGUGGUGGGCGCCUGUAGUCCCAGCUACUCGGGAGGCUGAGGCAGGAGAAUGGUGUGAACCCAGGAGGCGGAGCUUGCAGUGAGCCGAGAUAGUGCCUCUGCACUCCAGCCUGGGUGACAGAGCGAGACUCCGUCUCAAAAAAAAGGGCUGAUAAUGAUAAACAGUGAGCACUCCGGUCCUUUUUCUUAGGUUUUCCUUUUUUCCUUCCUCUCCACCCCACAAGUUUUGCUUUUUAACCAAGGUGUCUCUGCUUGAUGAAAUUCACAUGCUAGUCUAAAUCUUUUUUUCUCCCUUGUAACAUUUAUGUGCCCCAAACUGGUUAGUAUAUGGGUACAGCAUUCCCUUUCCAAUUGGGAAGCGGAAAAAGAGAGUAUGGGAUAUUUUAGAAGGGAGCCUUUGAACCUUAUUAUAUUUCCCCAUCAUUGAUAGUGACAAUCUUAAAAGGGUUGUUUUCUUACCUUAAGUACAAAAGCAUGGAAAAAUGCGCUUUUCCUUCCCGCCCACAUCACCACCCCGACUUGAAGACAGUAGGUGCUUGAAUGGAAAGUGAGUAGGCAUCUUUAAUCGCCCUGAUUAAAGGAAAGUGUUAGCCUGAGAGGGCCUGACUGAAAAGUAACCAAAGGCUUAAUAUCAAACACUAAUUAGCUUUUUAGUGCCUUAACCCUGACCUGGUUACCAGUUUUCUGUAGUUUCUACACCCAAGCCACUGAAGUCAUCUGUGGCCCAAGAGGUAGGACAAAAAAAAAAAAAAAAAAAGCUGAUUUCAAUAUUUGAUUUGUUGACAUCCCAAAAUGAAAGUUUUAUGUUUCCCUUAGAAACAUGUUUUGCUUGGUUCUAUAGUAUGUUACUUAGGAUCUAUUUACCAUAUAUUUGUAUGAGAAAUCCUCACCCAAGCAUUCAACCUAAAUCUUUGAAAAGUUGGGUGCUGUCUUUAGUAACUUUUAAAAUAGUUUAAAUCUCCCAUUUUAAUAGUGAUAAGGAAACCUGUUAAAAUCAUGGCUAUUGAUGUUAUAGUAUGGAAAGUUGAACUUUAUGAACCCAUACUUUUAAAAAGCAUUUUUAAAAAUCUAACACUGACUAUAGAAACAAAUUAAAAUGUCUACCUUUAAGUAUAAAAA